ACACUUGUGGCUUCCGUGCACACAUUAACAACUCAUGGUUCUAGCUCCCAGUCGCCAAGCGUUGCCAAGGCGUUGAGAGAUCAUCUGGGAAGUCUUUUACCCAGAAUUGCUUUGAUUCAGGCCAGCUGGUUUUUCCUGCGGUGAUUCGGAAAUUCGCGAAUUCCUCUGGUCCUCAUCCAGGUGCGCGGGAAGCAGGUGCCCAGGAGAGAGGGGAUAAUGAAGAUUCCAUGCUGAUGAUCCCAAAGAUUGAACCUGCAGACCAAGCGCAAAGUAGAAACUGAAAGUACACUGCUGGCGGAUCCUACGGAAGUUAUGGAAAAGGCAAAGCGCAGAGCCACGCCGUAGUGUGUGCCGCCCCCCUUGGGAUGGAUGAAACUGCAGUCGCGGCGUGGGUAAGAGGAACCAGCUGCAGAGAUCACCCUGCCCAACACAGACUCGGCAACUCCGCGGAAGACCAGGGUCCUGGGAGUGACUAUGGGCGGUGAGAGCUUGCUCCUGCUCCAGUUGCGGUCAUCAUGACUACGCCCGCCUCCCGCAGACCAUGUUCCAUGUUUCUUUUAGGUAUAUCUUUGGACUUCCUCCCCUGAUCCUUGUUCUGUUGCCAGUAGCAUCAUCUGAUUGUGAUAUUGAAGGUAAAGAUGGCAAACAAUAUGAGAGUGUUCUAAUGGUCAGCAUCGAUCAAUUAUUGGACAGCAUGAAAGAAAUUGGUAGCAAUUGCCUGAAUAAUGAAUUUAACUUUUUUAAAAGACAUAUCUGUGAUGCUAAUAAGGAAGGUAUGUUUUUAUUCCGUGCUGCUCGCAAGUUGAGGCAAUUUCUUAAAAUGAAUAGCACUGGUGAUUUUGAUCUCCACUUAUUAAAAGUUUCAGAAGGCACAACAAUACUGUUGAACUGCACUGGCCAGGUUAAAGGAAGAAAACCAGCUGCCCUGGGUGAAGCCCAACCAACAAAGAGUUUGUCCUCAGGACUACAGAAGCAGUUCACAUUUUACAGAUCAAACGGACGACACACACAUUCUUUCCACUGCAAAUUGUCCUUUCUCCACUAGAAGGUAAAACAGUUCUUGUUCAUACUCUGGUUUCCUCCCAAGCAUUGGCACAAGGAAGAAAAGAAAAAAUGGGAAAUGCUGAGCUGUAUAAUUUAUGGUUAUAAGAAGCUCCCUCUUUAAUAUUUCUGCCGCACUUUUUGGUAUCUUCAUGAUAAACAAAAGUUCCAUUAAAAUAAAUCACUUAUUUUUGUCCCAUGUUGUAAUUGUCUGUUUAGGUAUCAGUUUCUCCAAAUAAAUUGUAUCAACUUGAGGGCAGACACUUAAUUACAUCUUAUUAUCUCGAUCCCCAUCAUUGCAUAUCCAGAAAGAGCACAUAAAGCGUUUUUCAAUGGUAAGUACAAAGCUUUAGCUUUGUGCACCUUACAGUAGUUGAUCUAACCACUUAUUAGCUCCUAUUUAAAUAGAUGACACUCUUUUGUGUUAGAUAAUGUUAAAUUAGAAUAGACGAUUGGGGAAAAAAAGAUCCUUAUCUUAAAUGAAACUAUAACCUACUAAACUGUGGUAGAACUAAGAUGAAAUAUUAAAGUAAUAUUUCAAGGAGUAUUUACUAAUCCAUGUAUUGUCCAUAAGUGAUAUGCUUGAGAUGCAUAAUUUUGCUAACAAAAUAUCAUGAAGUGUAAUUAUUAAAUAUCUCUAUCAAUUACUGCAAUCCUGGUGCCCCAGUUGAGCUGGGCAAAAUUUCUAAAAUAUAAACACAUUAUUAAAAUCACAACAAAACAAAGAAAACUACCCUUAUAAAUCUCUGUAGUUUCGUGUUGUCAAAAAAUCAUAUGUAUAUUGCUGAGAGGCCCUUAAAAAGAAUAGGCCGUAAUAUUAUGAAAUAAUUAUCCAAAUGCACCCUCUAGUGGCUAAAAAGCAAUUCACAUAUGAGCUAAGCAAAACUGUGUUUAAAAUGAGGAGCAUUGAGUAACAUUUAACUGAAAUUUUUCUAAAUGAAAAUAAAAAUUGUGGCUUUAAUUUCUCCACAGCUCUAUUUAAUAAUAUAGUCAUUUGAAAAAAAUCAACGUACCUCAAUACUAAAAAAUACUUACCAUGUAAAAUACAUACACAUUCAAUGAAAAUAAAUACCCAAGUGUUCUGAUGAUUCUUUGUUAUCUGUGUUUUCUAAUAUUUUUUCAUCUCCAGAGCUUCUACUCAUGGUUAAAUGUUCACCUCUAACCUAAGGAAAAAAAUCAAACAUGUCUAAUCUGAAAUUUCACUAAAUUCCUUUUUAAUUUUAAAUGUGGUCUAAAAUAUUAUUCAUCACAAAUAACUUUGCCAUUAAACUGUAUAGCUCUUAACUAGAAACGUCCAUGUUUCCUAUUAACCUUGACAUCACAAAUGUUUGUGACUGCUAAAUAGUCUAUGAAGAUAAUGCCUUAAAAAACUUGUAACAAAAACAUUUCUAAUACUUUGAUGUCAGAAAACACUUCAAUAAAAUGGUAAUACAUUUUAAAAAGCUGAUGGCAUAAGAAUACAGCCAAUGAAAAGCUACUUUUUAUUUGUAAAAAUCUGUUAUUUUUGACUUCAAAUAUUUUAUUUAUAUUUCAUUAGGUUCCUAUCUUUCUAUGUAUGGCUAAAAGACAUCAGUGAAUACGAACUAGCAUUUUUAUGCUUCAUGUCUUUAUUGAAUAGGUUCAAAUAUGAAGACAUUAUUGGUGAAAAAACAAAAAACAAAUAGUGGACAAGAAAUAAUAGUCACCACAAUCAUCUUUUUCAACCUAACACAAUUCAGAAUAAUACAUAAGCAAUUUUUACAUUUUUAAUCUUACAAUCAUCUUUUAUUCUACCAUACUGUCAAAUACUUGUGAAAAUAAAUAAAAAUAAAAUACAUGAUG